AAGCUUCUACCUAUGCCCUGGCCUCGGAGCGAGCCCGAUAGCGCUGGAUCACAGCAGAGGGAGCGAGGCGGCUGACGUCCCAUCCCGAAGAGAUGAAUGGAAUUCCAGGAAGCUAGAGUCAUGCUGGCUUGGGACAGUGGCUUGGAGACCAGACUUCAAUGACAGAAGCACUAGGCAGCGGCACUCAUGGCAAUGUGUGCACCCACAGAAAUGUAACCCACACCUCGGGUUCAGGAGCCGAAAAAUGAAAAGAACGUUUAGGGAGGAAAAAGGGAAAUACAAUAAUAGGCAGAGAGUAAUUUAUUACUCUAUGGGUCUGCUCUGUAAAUAGCUGAAGACUCUGGAGCCAGAUGGUUCUGCAAAUUCUCCAAACAGGAGUCACGUUAAGAAGCACGAGUGGGCACAAAAACUGUUUUUCAAGACACAAUUUCAAUUUGGCUUGUGGAAACUGGAUACGAGUAAGUUUCCUUAAAAUUCGAGUAGAAAGCAGCUGUCCUCCCCGGGCCCCUUGAUGAGAAUACGCACACCGCCCCCAAGCGGCCGGCCGAGGGAGCGCCGCGGCAGCGGGAGAGGCGUCUCUGUGGGCCCCCUGGCAGCCGCGGCAGGAAAGGGCCCGAAGGCAGCGAAGGCGAACGCGGCGCACCAACCUGCCGGCCCCGCCGACGCCGCGCUCACCUCCCUCCGGGGCGGGCGUGGGGCCAGCUCAGGACAGGCGCUCGGGGGACGCGUGUCCUCACCCCACGGGGACGGUGGAGGAGAGUCAGCGAGGGCCCGAGGGGCAGGUACUUUAACGAAUGGCUCUCUUGGUGUCCCCUGCGCCCCGUCGGCCCAUUUUUCUUUUUACAAAACGGGCCCAGUCUCUAGUAUCCACCUCUCGCCAUCAACCAGGCAUUCCGGGAGAUCAGCUCGCCCGAAAGCCCCUGCGCCACCCCGCGGGCCCUCCUAGGUGGUCUCCCCAGCCCCGUCCCUUUUCGGGAUGCUUGCUGAUCACCCCGAGCCCGCGUGGCGCAAGAGUACGAGCGCCGAGCCCGUGCGCGCCAAGGCUGCGUGGGCGGGCACCGACUUUUCUGAGAAGUUCUAGUGCUCCCAAGCCCCGACCCCCGCCCCCUUCACUUUCUAGCUGGAAAGUUGCGCGCCAGGCAGCGGGGGGCGGAGAGAGGAGCCCAGACUGGCCCCCACCUCCCGCUU